AAUGGAGGGUCCGGCGUCCGCCUUGGCGGGUGGGAGUGAUGACCUGCACUCCCCAAACCACUGCGGGAUAGAACGGGGCCGAGUGCUCUCAGGGGUGGCCGCUACCGGGGCGGCCCGAGACACGGCUGCGGGUUCCAGCCAACAGGCCCGGAGUCGCGGCCUCGGCUCCGCCGUGGGUGCACGGGCUAGGGCUGCGGGGACUCCUGUGGGCUCCGCGUCUGCGGCUGGGAGGAAUGGGGAUCGUCCCCAGAUCCCGCCUUCCGGGCAGGGCCUCCGCUGCCUGCGAUCCUGCCCACAGUCCAAGGAUCCUCCUCGCCUCUCGCGGACUGCGGUGUCAGCCGCCCGAGCCGUUCCCCGGACACCUGGCCAGGGUCUUGCUGUCUCACCCAGGCUGGAGUGCAGUGGCACGAUCACAGCUCACUGCAGCCUUGAGCUCCUGGGCUACCAAGUAGCUGGGACUUCAGAGAUGGCUGGAGCCGUGUGGAUGGGCAUAAAUGGCUAAUGUCCAGCAACCAUCGAUGUCAAGUAUCCACACACCUGGCCUGAAUGGAUCCCUCUGCCUUUCAGAGACGGAGUCUCGCUCUGUCCCCCAGGCUGGAGUGCAAUGUUUGGGAUAUGAGAUUGAAAAUGACGACUCGGAAUUUUCCUGAGAGAGAAGUACCCUGUGAUGUAGAAGUGGAAAGAUUCACAAGGGAAGUUCCCUGCUUGUCCAGUUUAGGUGAUGGUUGGGACUGUGAGAACCAGGAGGGACACUUGAGGCAAUCAGCUUUAACUCUGGAGAAACCAGGGACUCAGGAAGCAAUUUGUGAAUAUCCUGGUUUUGGGGAGCAUUUGAUUGCAAGCUCAGACCUUCCACCGUCUCAGAGAGUUCUGGCAACAAAUGGUUUCCAUGCACCUGACUCAAAUGUUAGUGGUCUGGAUUGUGACCCCGCCUUACCCAGCUAUCCUAAAAGUUAUGCAGAUAAGAGAACUGGUGACAGUGAUGCCUGUGGAAAAGGCUUCAACCAUUCCAUGGAAGUUAUUCAUGGAAGAAAUCCAGUGAGAGAGAAGCCCUACAAAUACCCUGAAAGUGUUAAGUCUUUUAAUCAUUUUACCUCUCUUGGUCAUCAGAAAAUAAUGAAAAGAGGCAAGAAAUCGUAUGAAGGUAAGAAUUUUGAGAACAUCUUUACUCUGAGCUCAUCGCUUAAUGAAAACCAGAGAAAUCUCCCUGGAGAGAAACAAUAUAGAUGUACUGAAUGUGGCAAAUGCUUCAAACGGAACUCUUCUCUUGUUUUGCAUCACCGAACUCACACCGGAGAGAAGCCUUAUACUUGUAAUGAGUGUGGAAAGUCCUUCUCCAAGAACUACAACCUGAUUGUGCAUCAAAGAAUCCACACAGGAGAGAAGCCCUAUGAAUGCAGUAAAUGUGGGAAAGCUUUCAGUGAUGGCUCAGCUCUGACACAGCACCAGAGAAUUCACACAGGCGAGAAACCUUAUGAAUGCCUAGAGUGUGGAAAAACCUUCAACCGAAAUUCAUCCUUAAUUUUGCACCAAAGAACUCAUACAGGGGAAAAACCAUAUAGAUGUAACGAAUGUGGGAAACCCUUCACUGACAUCUCCCACCUUACAGUGCAUCUCAGAAUCCACACCGGUGAGAAGCCCUAUGAGUGUAGCAAAUGUGGAAAGGCUUUCCGGGACGGCUCGUACCUCACCCAGCAUGAGAGGACUCACACUGGAGAAAAGCCCUUUGAGUGUGCAGAGUGCGGGAAAUCCUUCAACAGAAACUCUCACCUCAUUGUGCAUCAAAAGAUCCAUUCUGGGGAGAAACCCUAUGAAUGUAAAGAAUGUGGCAAGACUUUCAUCGAGAGUGCGUACCUCAUCAGGCAUCAGAGGAUUCAUACUGGCGAGAAGCCCUAUGGCUGCAACCAGUGUCAGAAACUUUUCAGGAAUAUCGCUGGCCUCAUUAGGCACCAGAGGACUCAUACUGGUGAGAAGCCCUAUGAGUGUAAUCAGUGUGGCAAAGCCUUCAGGGACAGCUCCUGUCUGACCAAGCACCAGAGAAUUCACACUAAGGAGACCCCAUAUCAGUGUCCAGAAUGUGGGAAGUCCUUCAAGCAGAACUCUCACCUGGCAGUACAUCAGAGACUCCAUAGCAGGGAGGGUCCCAGCCGGUGUCCUCAGUGUGGAAAAAUGUUCCAAAAGAGCUCAUCCCUUGUUCGACAUCAAAGAGCACACCUGGGAGAGCAACCCAUGGAAACAUAAUGGUUGGGGGCCACAUGAGUCUUCCAGUUCACUCUCACUCCUGUGUUUAGGAGGCGUGUCUUAGAUCUGACUCCUCUCUGGUCAGUAGAAAAGAAUCCUUUAAGCUAUCCAGUGAAUUGAUGAAUGUGAGACAUUGCUGAGCCACACUGUUAAGUCUGCUCAUUGGGGAACUCCAGAGACAACUUAGGAUGAGGGCAGAAAAGUCUUUGGGGAUGAUUCAGUCUGUACCAGACAUGACAACACACACACUGGAAUGAAAUGUGCAAACAUGGGGGUGACACCACAGAGAGAACCUGUGAAUGCAUUCAGAACAUGAUUGGAAUGAAGAGCCCUGUAGUAGGGAGUUUCCACCUUGUACGUAAGCAAACACUGAAUCAACUUUUUUUUUUUUUUCGGACAGAGUCUCACUGUGCAGUGGCAUGAUCUCCACUCACAGCAACCUCUGCCUCCCAGGUUCAAGCAGUUCUCCUGCCUCAGCCUCCAAAGUAGCUAGGAUUACAGGUGCCUGCCACCAUGCCUGGCUAAUUUUUUCUAUUUUUAGUAGAGACAGGGUUUCACUGUGUUGGCCAGGCUGGUCUUGAACUCCUGACCUCAUGAUCCGCCCACCUCAGCCUCCCAAAGUGUUGGGAUUACAGGCAUGAGACACUGCCUGGCCUGAAUCAACCUUUUUUAAGUGUAAUCAGAAAGAGAGGCUUUGGCAGGGGCUCUUACUGUGUUUUCUGUAACAACAAAGGUGUACAAUGAGAGAGUCCACACAGUGCUGUACUGCACACACCACAGAAUGUGUGAGAUUUUCCUGUUUGAAUGUAUGUCUGCAUUAUACUCCUGCAAUAAUGCUGAGGACUCGUUGCAGGAGGGCAAACUAGGUGAAUAAAUUACCUGUGAAUGAACAAUGAAGUCGUUCCUCUUAAGACUGAAACAAGCAGGCCAGAUGUGGUGGCUCACGCCUGUAAUCCUAGCACUUUGGGAGGCCGAGGCGGCCAGAUCACAAGGUUAGGAGUUCAAGACCAGCCUGGCCAGCAUGGUGAAACCCCAUCUCUACCAAAAAUACAGGAAAUUAUCUGGGCAUAGUAGUGUGUGCCUGUAAUCCCAGCUACUUGGGAAGCUGAGGCAGGAGAAUUGCUUGAACCUGGGAGGUGGAGGUUGCAGUGAGCUAAGAUCGCACCACUGCACUCCAGCCUGGGUGACAGAGCGAGACUCCAUUUCAAAAAAAAAGACUGAAACAAGCUUGUGCUAAGAUGGAAAGGGCUGCUUCUAACAGAUGUGGUUUGUUGCUUUAGUUGUUGAAGCAAAAAUACUGAGUUGUUAUGUUUAUGUUAUCACCCCACCACUACCUCCAUGGUUGUUCAUUUAGGAUGCUUCUAAUUCAGCCACUGUGAACCAUUAUAAAGGUUUUAUUGCCAUGUUGAAAAUGUUUAUAAUAUGGCAAAAAGGGGCAUCAAAUAGAAGAUUUACUAUUAUUCCAGCCAUGUAAAAAUAUGUGCACAUAUGGAUGUAUGUUGAAAGUGGAUGAUGGAGAAAUAAAAUGUGGUUUUCUUUGGGGACUGGAAUUUUGUAUCAUAUUUUUUUCUCUGUUACAGAUACUUGUUGGCAUAAUAAUUUGGUAAUAAAUUAAAAAGUGAAGCCAAAA